AUUGUCGGGCUGCUGCUCUCAGCGGCGGGGCUCGCCAGCGCUUCAGUGGGCGGGGACGCGGCAGGUGAGACGGGGCGGGUACGGCCAGCUCGCUGAGCCCUCGAGGCGGGCGGCGGCAGGAAGGUGGUGCCUCGGCCCGUCGUGCCCUGUCGCCUAGCUCCAGCCGCGAUGCUGACCGCAAAGGCUGCCCUUCUGAGGCCUGGAAUGUGAGGCCCAGAGCGUCGGACCCAACUCAGCCUCGCCCGGAUGGGGAAAUCGAGGCAGGGAGCGGGGGUGGGCGUGCGUGGGGAUCCCUUGAAGGCAGCCUCGGAAACCCCACGGAGCCUGCGCUGCCUGGGCCCUGUGUGAGUCCAGGCUGUUGUUUCACUUCUGGUUUUAAGAUACUUUCCCUGUUCUGAGGUUUGAAGCCUCCCCUCCUCUGUUUUAAGUUCCGUGAUUCGGAGAAAACAAGUGAACUGACCGUGAAAAAGCCCGCGGGCUUCCAUGGAAUGCAGGCUGCCUGGGGUUGAACCCUGCUGGGUCCCGGUGUCGCCUCUACCCCCCAAUUAACUGCGCCCCUGGAACAGUUCCCUAACUGAUCUGCGCCUCAUAUGCCAAUCAUUGGGCUGUUGAGUGACUUGAAUUAGGUGAACUGAUGCAUUCCAACGUUGAUUCUUAUUGCCGAAUAAAUUGUUUGGAAAUUGCAAGUGGAAGUGUGCCUCGCUGAAUGAGAUUUUGGUGAACAAUACUUCUGAGUAAAAGUGUUGCUGGACAACGAAAAUUCGAGAUUAAUUUAACAGGUUUUUCCCCGGUGCUUAACUGGGUGUAAGCCAGACUUAGUUCUGGUCACUGGGUCAAAAUGGUAAACAAAAGACAGGCUUCCUGGCCUCAAGAAACUAAAAACAUAGUUCAAAUGGCACAGAACCACACCAGAGGUGACUCCAGACCAAGGAGGAUGAGCUGCUGUCCCUGGAAGAGAACGGAUGGAGGGAAGCAGCUCCUACGAAGUUCCCUCUGUGGCUGCUGCUGAUCUGGAGGAGGGUGCUGGUCAGACUAGGAGCUUGCCUGCCACCCCCUCCAAAGAUGUUCACAAGGGUGUUGGAGGCAUCAUCUUUUCCUCCUCACCGAUUUUAGACUUGAGUGAAAGUGGUCUGUGCCGUUUGGAGGAGGUCUUUAGAAUCCCCAGCCUUCAACAAUUGCAUCUGCAAAGGAAUGCCCUGUGUGUGAUUCCUCAAGAUUUCUUUCAGUUGCUUCCGAACCUGACUUGGCUGGACCUCCGGUACAAUAGAAUUAAAGCGCUUCCUUCUGGGAUUGGAGCUCACCAGCAUUUGAAAACUUUGCUUUUAGAAAGAAAUCCUAUCAAAAUGUUACCUGUGGAGCUGGGGAGCGUAACCACGCUGAAAGCACUGAACCUAAGACACUGCCCUCUGGAAUUCCCUCCUCAGCUCGUUGUGCAGAAGGGAUUGGUGGCUAUCCAGCGCUUCCUGCGGAUGUGGGCAGUAGAACACUCUCUCCCCAGAAAUCCAACUUCUCAAGAGGCUCCACCGGUUAGAGAGAUGACCCUCCGUGACCUCCCGAGCCCAGGACUGGAGUUGUCUGGAGACCACGCGUCUAACCAAGGAGCUGUGAACGCUCAGGACCCAGAGGGGGCUGUGAUGAAAGAGAAGGCCAGCUUUCUCCCACCUGUGGAAAAGCCAGACCUGAGUGAACUCAGGAAGUCUGCGGACUCCUCAGAGAACUGGCCCAGCGAGGAGGAGAUCAGGCGCUUUUGGAAGCUGAGGCAGGAGAUUGUUGAGCACGUGAAGGCAGACGUUCUGGGAGAUCAGCUCUUGACGAGGGAAUUACCUCCAAAUCUCAAGGCGGCCUUGAACAUUGAGAAAGAACUACCAAAGCCAAGACACGUUUUCAGAAGGAAGACAGCCUCCUCCAGGAGCAUCUUACCCGACCUCUUGUCACCGUACCAAAUGGCGAUCCGAGCAAAAAGACUGGAAGAGAGCCGAGCGGCGGCGCUCCGAGAGCUCCAGGAGAAGCAGGCUCUGAUGGAGCAGCAGAGACGAGAGAAAAGGGCACUGCAGGAGUGGAGAGAGCGAGCCCAGAGGAUGAGGAAGAGGAAGGAAGAGCUCAGCAAACUCCUGCCUCCGCGGAGGAGCAUGGUGGCAUCAAAGAUUCCCUCUGCCACAGAUCUGAUAGAUAACAGGAAAGUACCACUGAAUCCGCCUGGAAAAAUGAAACCAAGCAAAGAGAAAUCGCCACAAGCAAGUAAAGAAAUGAGUGCCCUGCAGGAGAGAAAUUUAGAAGAGAAGAUAAAACAGCACGUCCUCCAAAUGCGUGAGCAAAGAAGAUUCCAUGGCCAGGCCCCACUGGAGGAGAUGAGGAAGGCUGCCGAGGAUCUGGAAAUUGCCACAGAGCUACAGGAUGAAGUAUUGAAGCUAAAAUUGGGAUUAACCUUGAACAAAGAUCGUCGACGGGCGGCCCUCACUGGAAACCUUUCGCUUGGCCUGCCGGCAGCACAGCCUCAAAAUACAUUUUUUAACACAAAAUAUGGAGAAUCAGGAAAUGUUCGCAGAUACCAGUGACACCAGGUGGCUGGACUGAUGGAGACGUCUUCAGACAGGAGCCGCUCAGUCUUCUUUCCCGGGCGUCGCCUCCUGUGUGGUGCCGGAAGAGCGCCAGGUUCAGUGUUACCCUGAGGGCUGAUUUCGCGCAGCCUGUUGUUUUCCUUAGACAGGUCCACGUCCCUCUCCUGAGGCUGUGGAAGAUUUCAGCCGUAUUAAAAGAAAGGACACUGUGAGCACGUGGUCUCGCCUUCCCUUCUUCCUGCAGGUUCCCGCCAAGCCAUGUGACAGAGUGCUCACACUCAGGCACUUGCCUCUCUCCUGUCCUGGAGCCCUUGUUACAAAAGUACUCACAGCUUUCCUUCACUUAGUUAUUUGAGUGUGGGAGAGGAGACCAGGUCACCCGAUUCCCGCCAAGCCGGAAGUCCCUGCAGCACCACCUUUGGCUAGGAGGGAGGGGUGACAGCCAAAAAGGGCUUCGGGGGAGUGGUUACCCUGCUCCCUGCCCAGUGACAAGCCCUCCUUUCCCCUGGGGGCCCUCCUUUCCCCUGCUCCCUGCCCAGCUACGGGGCCCUCCUUUCAGCCUUGACCCCUUCCUGGUUGCUACCACUCAGGCUGCCACUCAGUGGACUCCACCCCAGGGACACGGCAGGGUCUGCAGACCUCCCCAUGCUAGAUCAGCCGUAUUUCAUGCUCUGUCUGCCCAGGCUGUGUAGAUUCUGUGUGACUUAGUCUCUUGUGCUGAGUGUUUGCUUGGAUCUUGAAAACAUCUUUGGUUUGAUUUCUUUAACAGAGGUGAGACUAUUCAGACUUUGUUUAUUUUUGUGUUAAUUUUGGUAAAUAUGGUUUCAGUGAGUUUCCUCAUUUCAUCCAAGUUGUGCAAUGUAUCAGCAUAAAGUUCCUCUUAUUUUCAGUAUCUUUAGGAUCCGUAAUAAUGUCCCCUCUUUUAUUCUUGACCUGGUGUUCUUCAUCAUUCUUGCUAUGGAUUUAUCAAUUUUGUUCCUCUUUUCCAAAAGCCCCAGGUUUUGGCUUCACUGGAUUUGCUGUUUGUCUUCUGUCUCAUGGGUCUCUGCGCCCUGCACUUCGUACUUUCCGAGAGUUUAACUGGUGCUUAGAGAGAAAUGCAUCACUUCCAAACCCAUGUAUUAGAGAAGAAGGGCGUGAAAUUUAUCACCUAAGCUUUCCAUUCAGGAAGCUAGAAAAGGUGUCAGUGACCUGUUGCGGCCCAGCGGCUGGAGCAGCAGACGUUUGCCAUUUCUCACGCCUGAGGGCAGGCGUUGGAGCAGCUCAGCCGGCGUUGCUGGUCAGGGUCUCCCGUGAGGCUGGAGUCAGCCGUGGGUUGAGCUGCUCUCCUCUGAAGGUUUAACUGGGCUUGGGGCUCAGCUUCCAAGGUGCUCACCUGGUUGUUGAUCAGAGAGCGUGUCCGUUGUGAUCCCAGUCCUUUGAAACUGUGAAGCCUCGCCCCGCGGCCUGCCGCAGGAUAUGUUUUGGUAAAUGUAGACUGUGCACUUGAGAAGAAUGUAUUUUGAGUUGUUGGGUACAUUGUUUUGUGUGUGUCAGGUGACAUUGACUAAUCCUGUUGCUCAGAGCUCCUGUACCCUUACUGACUGACUUAAGCCUGGUUUCUCAGUUACUGAGAGAGGCCUGUGAACAGUUCUAGCUAUGAUCAUGAACAUGUGUUUUCUUCUUAGUUAUGUGAGUUUUUGCUAUACGUGUUUUGGGGCUAUUUUGUCAGAUGCCUACAAAUUUAGGAUUGUUUUAUCUUCCUGUCGAACUGACCUUGUCAUUAUUAUGAACUAUUUCUCUUCGCCUCUCCUUUUCACUUCUUGCCUUCUGUGGAUUUUGUCUGAUACUAAUCCAGGCACACUGCUGCUGUUUUGGUCAGCGUUUUCAUAAUGCAUCUUCUUCCCUCCUUCUACUGUACUGGAUUUAAAGCGCACCUUAUAGAGACAUCAUAUACUCGGGACUCCUUUUCUUUCUCUAGCUGCCAGUUCUGUGUUUCAGUUACAGUGUUUGGCCCUCACAUUUAAGGUGCGUGUGCGUACGGCGGAUUCCGUGCCCAUCUCAUGUUUUUAUUCCCUUUAUUCUUCUUUUGCUGCUUUCUGAUAGUGAUCAAUUUUUUUAUUUAUAUCUCUUGUAUUAGAGUUUUAGUAAUAUCUUUUAAUAUUAUUCUCUUGGGUGUUGCCUUAGAGAUUUCAUACAUGCCCUUGAGUUCAUUAGCAUUUCCUGAAUGAGCCAAUGACCCUGAGAAGGUCCCUCCCAUCUGCCAGUUCCCUGCCAUUGAUGCUGUUGCUCUCGUCCGCCUCCCUUCCACAGGUAAGCACGCAAGACACAGGUACCGUGUGCCCCAACGGUGUCUUGACUCGCUGUUCCUAGACAUCAGUGUUUGCUUCACUUUACCCAUCCCGAUGCUCUUCCUUCCUGCAGCUUCAUGCUCCAAUGAGGGCUGAUUUUCAUUUAGCUAAAUAACUUUUUUUUAAGUAUUUCUUUGUAUCAUGGUUAUGCUUUGACUGGCCGUAAGUUCUCUCAGCUUUUGUUUGUCUGAAAAUAAAUUUAGUUCGCCUUUAUUCUGCACAGGACAGAAUUCUAGGUGGAUGAUUUUUGCCAUUCCCAGAACUUUAAAGAUGGGCUCCACUGUCUUCUGGCUCCCAUGUGUUUUGUUAAAAAUUCAGUGUUCAGGCCGGGUGCUGUGGCUCACGCCUGUAAUCCCAGCACUUUGGGAGGCCGAGGCGAGUGGAUCACGAGGUCAGGAGAUCGAGACCAUCCUGGCUAACACGGUGAAACCCCGUCUCUACUAAAAAAUACAAAAAAUUAGCCGGGCGUGGUGGCUGUAGUCGCAGCUACUCAGGAGGCUGAGGCGGGAGAAUGGCGUGAACCCAGGAGACGGAGCUUGCAGUGAGCCGAGAUCGCGCCACUGCACUCCAGCCUGGGCGACAGAGCGAGACUCCGUCUCAAAAAAAAAAAAAAAAGAUUCAAUGUUCAUUGUUAUUUGUUGCUCCUUUGAAGGUAAUGGGUCUUUUUUCUUUGUCUUAAAAUUGUUUCUCCUUAUCUUUGGUUUUCAGCAGUCUGUGCUGUGCCUGGAUGUAAUUUUCUUUUUACGUAUUUUUCUUGGAAUAUACAGAACUCAAAUCUGGGAGUUAGCAUCUUUCAUCAGUUUUGGAAAAUUCUUAGCCAUUUUUUUUUUUUUUACUAUUUUUUCCCCUGUUCUCCCUCUUCUCCCUGAGACUUCAGUUUUGUGUGUGUGUGCACAUGUGUGUAUGCAUUCGUGCGUACGAGUGUGUGCAUGUGUGCGCCCGUGUGUAUGUGCAUAUGUGAGUGUGUGUGGCUGUAACCUGCACGUCUCUUCUGUCAUGUGUUCUAUUUUUCAUUCCUCUCUGUACAUCAGGCUAGAUGCCUCCUGUCUACGUGGUUUUAGAUUUACGAAUCCUGUCUUCUGUUGUGUCCCACAGAAAAACCCAUGAGGUUUUUUAACAUUAAAAACAGCAGCUUUAUGAUAGAGAAAAAAACACAAACAUAGACGAUUGUACCAUUGCACUCAGAAGAAACAUCCCAGGCCCUGAGCAGCGUGUCUUUCCUCGGCCGAGUCAGGCUUCCUGGUGAGCCUCAGGGAGUGCAUGGUCUCAGAUGCCAUCCUUCUCUUCUCCAGCAUUUCCACUCACCUCCGUGUUCUUGGGGAGUGCGUGGUGUCAGAUCCCAUCCUGCUCCUCUCCAGAGUUUCCGGUCACCUCCGUGUUCUCAGGGAGUGCGUGGUCUUGGAUGCCAUCCUGCUCAUCUCCAGCAUUUCCUCUCACCUCCGUGUUCUCGGGGAGUGCGUGGUGUCAGAUCCCAUCCUGCUCAUCUCCAGCAUUUCCUCUCACCUCUGUGUUCUCGGGGAGUGCGUGGUGUCAGAUCCCAUCCUGCUCCUCUCCAGCAUUUCCUCUCACCUCCGUGUUCUCGGGGAGUGCGUGGUGUCAGAUCCCAUCCUGCUCCUCUCCAGAGUUUCCUCUCACCUCCGUGUUCUCGGGGAGUGCGUGGUCUCAGAUCCCAUCCUGCUCCUCUCCAGAGUUUCCUCUCACCUCCGUGUUCUCAGGGAGUGCGUGGUCUUGGAUGCCAUCCUGCUCAUCUCCAGCAUUUCCUCUCACCUCCGUGUUCUCGGGGAGUGCGUGGUGUCAGAUCCCAUCCUGCUCCUCUCCAGCAUUUCCUCUCACCUCCGAGCUCUCGGGGAGUGCGUGGUCUCAGAUCCCAUCCUGCUCCUCUCCAGAGUUUCCUCUCACCUCCGUGUUCUCGUUCUCAUCUCUGCCGGAAUUCCACAUCUGCUCGUGCAUGCCAUCCACCUUUUCCACUAGAUCCUUUUACAUCAUCAUUAUAAUGAUUUUUUUUUAAUAAGUGUUUUCUUUCAGUUUUAAAUUUCAGAUGUUGUGUUUUUCAGGUCUAAGGUGUCUGGUAAUUUUUUGUGGAUGCCGAUUCUCUGUUGAAAUUCUCCAUCUUUUCAUUUCCUUUAUAUCUCUUUUCUUCUUUUUUCUAUAAUAUAUUACAUUUUUCUAAUAAGUUUUUAGUGAGUGUCCAGCAUUGUAUAAGUUGACCCUUGAACAAGAGUUUGAAUUAUAAGGGUCCACUUAUAAGUGGAUUUUUAAAAAAAUAUAUAUUGCAAAAAUUUUUGGAAAUUUGCAACAAUUUGAAAAACUUUGCAGAUGAGCCACAUAGCCUAGAAAUAUCUGAAAAAAGAAAAAGUUAUGUCAUGAAUGCAUAAAAUAUACAGACCAUACAUGGACCAUUCACAGUAGAGAGAAAUGUCGCCGUAAAGAUGCAGCAUUGGCCGAGUGCAGUGGCUCACGCCUGUAAUCCCAGCACUUUGGGAGGCCGAGGUGGGCAGAUCACCUAAGGUCAGGAGUUCAAGACCAGCCUGGCCAACAUGGAGAAACCCCGUGACUACUAAAAAUAAAAAAUUAGCCAGGCAUGGUGGCACAUGCCUGUAACUCCAGCUACUUGGGAGGCUGAGGCAGGAGAAUCACUUGAACCCGGAAGGCAGAGGUUGCAGUGAGCCGAGAUCACGCCAUUGCACUCCAGCCUGGGCAACAAGAGCAAAACUCUGUCUCAAAAAAAAAAAAAUGCAGCAUUAAAUUAUAACUGCAUGAAAUUAACUGCAGUCCACAGUGUGCUGCUGGAAUAAUUACAAAGCCACCUCCUGUUGCUAUUGCAGUGAGCGCAAGCAUGUCAAGGAUCCGCUUAAAACAUCGUGUGGUGCUAAUCUCUGCACGAGCGGUUCAUGUCUUCAGUACAUUGUGUAUCACGGUAAAAAGUGAUCUGUUUUAACUGGACAUGGUGGCACACGCCUGCAGUCCCAGCUACUCAGGAGGCUGAGGCAGGAGGAUCCCUUGAGCCCAGGAGGUCGAGGCUGCAGUGAGCUGUGAUUGCACCACUGCACUCAAGCCUGGGCAACAGAGUGAGACCCCAACUUGAAAAAAAGGGGACAUCGGGAUGUUCUUGUGUAUUUUUCAUGUUGAGCGCAAUACUGUAAACCUUGAAGAACACUUUGGGACCCAUAGAGUGCCACCAGUCAUGCCAAAGAGCUCCUGAGAAGCAGAGAAAAGUCAUGACAUUUCAAGAAAAAGUUGAAUUUCUUGAUAUGUUCCGUAGAUUGAGGUUUACAGCUGCGGUUGCCUACCAAUUCAAGAUAAAUGAAUCCAGCGUAAGGACCAUAGUAAAAAAAUAAGGAAAUUUGUGAGCAGGCACAAAAGCCUUAACACUUUCUGUGAAAUACCUUUUUAUCUUGUAUUGGGAAUGCAGCUUUUAUGUGGGUAUAGGAUUGCUGUGUGUGAUGGUUCAUAUUAAAUGUCAACUUGAUUAGAUUGAAGAAUGUAAAGUAUUGUUUCUGGGUGUUGCCAGAAGAGAUUAACAUUUGAGUCAGUGGACUGGGAGAAGACCCACCACAGUGUGGGCAGGCACCAUCCAGUCGGCUGCCAGCAUGGCUGGAAAAAGCAGGCAGAAGAAGGUGGCUGAAGCUGACUGGCUGAGUCUUCUGGCCUUCAUCUCUCUCCCAUGCUGGAUGCUUCCUGCCCUUGAACAUCAGACUCCAAGUUCUUUAGCUUUUGGACUCUUGGACCUACACUGGUGUUUUGCCAGGGGCUCUCGGGCCUUCGGCCACAGACUGAAGGCUGCACUGUCGGCUUCCCUCCUUUAGAGGUUUGGGGACUCAGACUGAGCUACUACUGGCUUCCUUGCCCCUCAGUUUGCAGACAGCCUAUUGUGGGACUUCACCCUGUGAUCCUGUGCCUCAGUUCUCCUUAAUAAACUCCAUUUCAUAUGUA